UAACCUAAAGAAAAACAACCAGACAAGUGCCCAACGACACUUAAAAAGGUGAUUUAUUAUCUUGCCAAGUUUAGGCUGGGCAUGGUGACUCAUGCCUCUAAUCCCAGCAUUUUGGGAGGCUGAGGCUGGUGGAUCACCGGAGGCCAGGACUUUGAGACCAGCCUGACCAAUAUGGCAAAACCUCGUCCCUACUAAAAAUACAAAAAUUAGCCGGGCAUGGUGGUGUGAGCCUGUAGUCCCAGCUACUCAGGAGGCUGAGACAGGAGAAUUGCUUAGAUUCAGGAGGUGGGGGUUUUAGUGGGCCGAGAUCACGCCAUUGCACUCCAGACUGUGCGACAGAGCGAGACUCUGUCAAAAAAAAAAAAAAAAAAUUAUCCUGCAAAAUUUGAAAAGGAAAUUCAAAUCAACAGCUUCUAAACUACUUUUUAACAUGACUCAUAAUAAUACAUUCUAUAGUACAUAUGUAUGUUCUAUAACUUUGAAUAAAAGAGUUAACCACAUCACAUUUAUUUUAUAACAUGUAAUACAUAUUUUUUAUUCUCCUUCAUUUGUUUUGAAUGCUCUGUGCAGUCUACAAAAAGUCCAAUAGUAAUAAUUAAAUUAGUCAUUAAGUUGAACAUUAUCUUGUCUUUUAAAAUGAUAAUCUCAAAAAUGAUCUUUUAUUUUUGAGAUUUAUAUAGAUACACACACACACACACACACACACACACACACACACACACACACACACACACACACACAUAUUUUUUGAGACAGAGUUUCACUCUGUCCCCCAGGCUGGAGUGCAAUGGCACAAUCUUGGCUCACUGCAACCUCUGUCUCCCGGGUUCAAGCAAUUCCUCUGCCUCAGCCUCUGAGUAGCUGGGACUACAGGUGUGUGCCACCAUGCCCAGCUAAUUUUUGUAUUCUUAGUAGAGAUGGGGUUUCACCAUAUUGGCCAGGCUCGUGUCAACUCCUGACCUCGUGAUCUGCCCACCGCGGCCUCCCAAAGUGCUGGGACUAUAGGUGUGAGCCGCUGCACCCGGUCCAAGUAAAAUUAUUUUAACAAUAUACUAUGAAGAGAAAAACACUGGCUAUGAAAGAAUAUGCAUAGUUUUACCCUGUUUAAAAAUAAAGAUUGAAAGAAUACAUAUGCAAAUAAGUUUACUUUUAUUUUUGGUAACACUUUACUGCAUUGUCUGAAUAUUGACAAUCAGUAUGCAUUAUGAAGCUACCUGGCUAACAUUGUGUACUCACUGUGUGUGCCAGGCCCUGGGUUCAAUGCUCUACAUGCACUUAUAUUUCAUUUAAUUCUCUCUGCAACCUGAGAUGGUAUAGCCACCUCAUUUUACAGAGUUGAAACUGAGGCUCAGAGACUGAAAGUUAAGCCUGAGGUUGCAGUCAAUAAGAGGCAGAGCUGGAACUGAAACCUACCUGUGUCUGACCACCAGUUCGUGUUCUGACGGCAGGCUAGUCUGCAUCACAGAGUGUGGAGUAGAUGGUGCAUGCCUGCUAGGAUGGGCUAGGUAUCACUGUAGGUAAGAAACAGCCCCAAACUAUGGAAAUGUACACCACUGAAGGCUCUUUUCCUGCCCAUGCUGCACAUCCUCCAUGGCUCUCCUGUGCCCUGUGCCCCACAUGCCCUCAUCCUGCCACGAGAAUAAAGGAGCAGCCUCCAUAUGGGAGCUGUCAGCUGCUCUAAGAGAUGAAGGAGAGAGUGGCCCGUCUCAAUGGCUCCCAACUCUUUUGCCUCGAGGUGACACGCUUCACUUCCACGCACAUCUCCUGGGUCAAAGCAAAUCCCAUGGGUACAUCCACUUUCAAGUGGCCCAGGAGAGAACCUGAAAUACUCGGUGGACUCCAUUAAGGCCGUCAUAUGGUGUCAGCCUGCAUGGGAGACUGUGGAGGGGCAGAGGAGGAGAGUGGGGAACUGAUGGGAAAUGACAGGAGGACUAAGUCACCGCAGAUUUGCUUUAUCUUCAGCCAGGUGGAGUUUGUCCCAGAGCCGCACAAAAUCAUCACCAGCAUGAUUAAACGGAGUAGACUUCAGAAAAAGCAGUUUGGUCGGAUGUAAUCAGCAGUGAACUCAGAAUCAAUUGAGUGACAUUGAGUCAGUAAAUCUCUGACUGCCUCAGUUACCCCAUAUGAUAGUUUUGAGGAUGGGAACAUUGAGAGAGUUGAUUUGGAAGGAUAUCAAGAGUAAAAAUUCCAACAUUUUUAGUUCCUUUAAGUUAAAUCCAGGCACUGUCUUUCCUGCAAGUCUCCUGUUCCUUUCAGAUUGCACAGGUGAGAGUGCUCAGAUUAGGGCUGGAGGUUGUAAACCAUUGCUCCCACACUGACAGUGCCCCCGUGUCGUGCGUGUAUUCUGCGCAUUUUCCUGUGCUAAACACUCUCCCAAAACAUCGUGGGGCCUGAUUCUUCCUCUUUGUUCCAAUGGCCCUGGGUGACUCAAGUGCCCAUUCAAUGACCAGGACACAGAGGUCUUAGAGAGAUGCUCCUUGAGGCCCCAGGUGCGAGCCUGUACCCUGCCGGAGCAUGAGGCAAGGGACAGGGCAUCGUCUGUGGGGAUAGUGGGGGUAGUGGGGGUAGUGGUCAGCCAGAUUUGGUGACUCUACUUGCUCACCAGACGAUCCUACACCUGCCACCUCCGAUGGAUCCACUGCCUCUGUGCCUGCCUGUACUGCUGAUGCUCCAGUGGAUAACUCAGCAUCCCAGCCUAGGCCCAAUGCCACUGAAGAUGGACCUGCCCCCUGGGGACCCAGGAGUCCUACCACUCAGCUGUCCCCAGGAGUGCCCAGACCCUCAUUCUUAUCCAGGACCUAGGAGCCCUACCCCUGGCCUUCCCUCAUCAGCCGUAAAUGAUGAUUUACUGCUGUUACCAUCAUCACUGCCUUCAGUGACCAAGGGCCUUCCAAGGUGCCAGCUCUGGAACGAAGGAUGCCCUUGGGAGGUGAUGACACUCAGGUUGAUGGACGGAUGGCUACAUGGAUGUGAUGGAGAUGGUUUACUAUCGGGACCUUCCGCACCCUGCUGAUGUUUUGUUGCUUAGGAUAUGAAUGGCUGAGCGGAGGCUGUAAAACCUGGCACUCUGCUUGGGUUAUCAAUACUCUGGCUGACCAUCAUCAUCGUGGGACUGACUUUGGUGGAAGUCCUUGGUUACAUGUCAUUAUUGCAUUUCCGACAAGUUAUAAAGUUGUCAUUACCCUCUGGAUAGUUUACCUUUGGGUGUCUCUCCUGAAGACUAUCUUCUGGUCUCGAAAUGGACAUGAUGGAUCCACGGAUGUACAGCAGAGAGCCUGGAGGUCCAACCGCCGUAGACAGGAAGGGCUGAGGUCCAUUUGUAUGCACACAAAGAAAAGAGUUUCUUCCUUUCGAGGAAAUAAAAUUGUCCUGAAAGACGUCAUUACUCUACGGAGACAUGUGGAAACAAAAGUUAGAGCUAAAAUCCGUAAGAGGAAGGUGACAACGAAAAUCAACCAUCAUGACAAAAUCAAUGGAAAGAGGAAGACCGCCAGAAAACAGAAAAUGUUUCAACGUGCGCAAGAGUUGCGGCGGCGAGCAGAGGACUACCACAAAUGCAAAAUCCCCCCUUCUGCAAGAAAGGCUCUUUGCAACUGGGUCAGAAUGGCGGCAGCGGAGCAUCGUCAUUCUUCAGGAUUGCCCUACUGGCCCUACCUCACAGCUGAAACUUUAAAAAACAGGAUGGGCCACCAGCCACCUCCUCCAACUCAACAACAUUCUAUAACUGAUAACUCCCUGAGCCUCAAGACACCUCCCGAGUGUCUGCUCACUCCCCUUCCACCCUCAGCGGAUGAUAAUCUCAAGACACCUCCCGAGUGUGUGCUCACUCCCCUUCCACCCUCAGCGGAUGAUAAUCUCAAGACACCUCCCGAGUGUGUGCUCACUCCCCUUCCACCCUCAGCGGAUGAUAAUCUCAAGACACCUCCUGAGUGUCUCCUCACUCCCCUUCCACCCUCAGCGGAUGAUAAACUCAAGACACCUCCCGAGUGUCUGCUCACUCCCCUUCCACCCUCAGCUCUACCCUCAGCUCCACCCUCAGCGGAUGAUAAUCUCAAGACACGUGCCGAGUGUCUGCUCCAUCCCCUUCCACCCUCAGCGGAUGAUAAUCUCAAGACACCUUCCGAGCGUCAGCUCACUCCCCUUCCACCCUCAGCUCCACCCUCAGCAGAUGAUAAUAUCAAGACACCUGCCGAGCGUCUGCGGGGGCCGCUUCCACCCUCAGCGGAUGAUAAUCUCAAGACACCUUCCGAGCGUCAGCUCACUCCCCUUCCACCCUCAGCUCCACCCUCAGCAGAUGAUAAUAUCAAGACACCUGCUGAGCGUCUGCGGGGGCCGCUUCCACCCUCAGCGGAUGAUAAUCUCAAGACACCUUCCGAGCGUCAGCUCACUCCCCUUCCACCCUCAGCUCCACCCUCAGCAGAUGAUAAUAUCAAGACACCUGCCGAGCGUCUGCGGGGGCCGCUUCCACCCUCAGCGGAUGAUAAUCUCAAGACACCUUCCGAGCGUCAGCUCACUCCCCUUCCACCCUCAGCUCCACCCUCAGCAGAUGAUAAUAUCAAGACACCUGCCGAGCGUCUGCGGGGGCCGCUUCCACCCUCAGCGGAUGAUAAUCUCAAGACACCUUCCGAGCGUCAGCUCACUCCCCUUCCACCCUCAGCUCCACCCUCAGCAGAUGAUAAUAUCAAGACACCUGCCGAGCGUCUGCGGGGGCCGCUUCCACCCUCAGCGGAUGAUAAUCUCAAGACACCUUCCGAGCGUCAGCUCACUCCCCUUCCACCCUCAGCUCCACCCUCAGCAGAUGAUAACAUCAAGACACCUGCCUUCCACCCUCAGCGGAUGAUAAUCUCAAGACACCUUCCGAGCGUCAGCUCACUCCCCUUCCACCCUCAGCUCCACCCUCAGCAGAUGAUAAUAUCAAGAUACCUGCUGAGCGUCUGCGGAUUCCGCUUCCACCAUCAGCCGAUGAUAAUCUCAAGACACCUUCCGAGCGUCAGCUCACUCCCCUUCCACCCUCAGCUCCACCCUCAGCAGAUGAUAAUAUCAAGACACCUGCCGAGCGUCUGCGGGGGCCGCUUCCACCCUCAGCGGAUGAUAAUCUCAAGACACCUUCCGAGCGUCAGCUCACUCCCCUUCCACCCUCAGCUCCACCCUCAGCAGAUGAUAAUAUCAAGACACCUGCCGAGCGUCUGCGGGGGCCGCUUCCACCCUCAGCGGAUGAUAAUCUCAAGACACCUUCCGAGCGUCAGCUCACUCCCCUUCCACCCUCAGCUCCACCCUCAGCAGAUGAUAAUAUCAAGACACCUGCCGAGCGUCUGCGGGGGCCGCUUCCACCCUCAGCGGAUGAUAAUCUCAAGACACCUUCCGAGCGUCAGCUCACUCCCCUUCCACACUCAGCUCCACCCUCAGCAGAUGAUAAUAUCAAGACACCUGCCGAGCGUCUGCGGGGAGCGUCUGCGGGGGCCGCUUCCACCCUCAGCGGAUGAUAAUCUCAAGACACCUUCCGAGCGUCAGCUCACUCCCCUUCCACCCUCAGCUCCACCCUCAGCAGAUGAUAAUAUCAAGACACCUGCCGAGCGUCUGCGGGGGCCGCUUCCACCCUCAGCGGAUGAUAAUCUCAAGACACCUUCCGAGCGUCAGCUCACUCCCCUUCCACCCUCAGCUCCACCCUCAGCAGAUGAUAAUAUCAAGACACCUGCCGAGCGUCUGCGGGGGCCGCUUCCACCCUCAGCGGAUGAUAAUCUCAAGACACCUUCCGAGCGUCAGCUCACUCCCCUUCCACCCUCAGCUCCACCCUCAGCAGAUGAUAAUAUCAAGACACCUGCCGAGCGUCUGCGGGGGCCGCUUCCACCCUCAGCGGAUGAUAAUCUCAAGACACCUUCCGAGCGUCAGCUCACUCCCCUUCCACCCUCAGCUCCACCCUCAGCAGAUGAUAAUAUCAAGACACCUGCCGAGCGUCUGCGGGGGCCGCUUCCACCCUCAGCGGAUGAUAAUCUCAAGACACCUUCCGAGCGUCAGCUCACUCCCCUUCCACCCUCAGCUCCACCCUCAGCAGAUGAUAAUAUCAAGACACCUGCCGAGCGUCUGCGGGGGCCGCUUCCACCCUCAGCGGAUGAUAAUCUCAAGACACCUUCCGAGCGUCAGCUCACUCCCCUUCCACCCUCAGCUCCACCCUCAGCAGAUGAUAAUAUCAAGACACCUGCCGAGCGUCUGCGGGGGCCGCUUCCACCCUCAGCCGAUGAUAAUCUCAAGACACCUCCCUUAGCUACUCAGGAGGCUGAGGCAGAAAAACCACGCAAACCCAAGAGGCAGAGGGCGGCUGAGAUGGAACCACCUCCCGAACCCAAGAGGCGGAGGGUCGGUGACGUGGAACCGUCACGCAAACCCAAGAGGCGGAGGGCCGCUGACGUGGAACCAUCAUCACCCGAACCCAAGAGGCGGAGGGUCGGUGAUGUGGAACCGUCACGCAAACCCAAGAGGCGGAGGGCCGCUGACGUGGAACCAUCAUCACCCGAACCCAAGAGGCGGAGGGUCGGUGACGUGGAACCGUCACGCAAACCCAAGAGGCGGAGGGCCGCUGACGUGGAACCAUCAUUACCCGAACCCAAGAGGCGGAGGUUGAGCUGAGAAGAGGCCAGUGCACUCAAGCCUGAGCAAUAAGAAUAAAACCGAGUAGAACAAAAUAAAAAAUUCAAAAAACAAAACAAAACCCACACUCCAAAAACUAACAAAGAAUAAAUAAAUAAUAUAAAAAUAAAAUAAA